GCGCGGGCUGCGCGUCGCCAUGGAGCCCGACGGGACUUACGAGCCGGGCUUCGUGGGUAUUCGCUUCUGCCAGGAAUGUAACAACAUGCUGUACCCCAAGGAAGACAAGGAGAACCGCAUUCUGCUCUACGCGUGCCGGAACUGUGAUUACCAGCAGGAGGCCGACAACAGCUGCAUCUAUGUCAACAAGAUCACGCACGAAGUGGACGAACUGACCCAGAUUAUCGCCGACGUGUCCCAGGACCCCACGUUGCCGCGGACCGAGGACCACCCGUGCCAAAAGUGCGGCCACAAGGAGGCUGUGUUCUUCCAGUCACACAGUGCGCGGGCCGAGGACGCCAUGCGCCUUUACUACGUGUGCACAGCCCCACACUGCGGCCACCGCUGGACCGAGUGACCUCCUCUCUCCCCCGAGUGUAAUAAACACCAGAUUCCAUGCGUGA